CUGUUUGGCGGCCAUUUCUCUUGAAACUGCGGCUCGGGACCUGCGGUACCUGCUGUAGUCACGAGGGACGGGCGGCGGCCUGGUCGGCAGAGAGUAGCCUGCAACAUUCGGCCGUGGUUACGAUGAGUUUACCCCUCAAUCCCAAACCUUUCCUCAAUGGACUAACAGGAAAGCCAGUGAUGGUGAAACUUAAGUGGGGAAUGGAGUACAAGGGCUAUCUGGUAUCUGUAGAUGGCUACAUGAACAUGCAGCUUGCAAAUACAGAAGAAUACAUAGAUGGAGCUUUGUCUGGACAUCUGGGUGAAGUUUUAAUAAGGUGUAAUAAUGUCCUUUAUAUCAGAGGUGUGGAAGAAGAGGAAGAAGAUGGGGAAAUGAGAGAAUAGCAUCUUUUGUGGGGGAUUUUUUUUAUAUAUAUUUCUAGACAAUAAAGAUUUGUUUGUUUUUCAACUUGA